AGUUCGGGGCAGCUUCUCCGGCUGGUGGGUGGGUGGGGCAGCCUUUCAGGCAGGUAUGCAUGGGAGGUGGGGAUCGGAACGGGGUGUUUCGACUGCAACCGCCUGGAGACCUGGCCGGUACCAUUCUCCAUAGUGCAGAUGGGGAAACAGGGUUGGAGAGAGGGGGCCUCAUCUGGGUCGUUAACAAUGCGGUGCGUAGCUGUGAGGGAGUUUACACUUCUGACUUCGGGCCUUGGCUCCUGGGACGGCGCACUGGUGCAAGAGCCGCUUCUGGAGUCUGGUGGACUCGGGUUCGUGUCUUGCCUGGGACAGUCUUUUUUUUCUUUUUUUUGAGACGGAGUCUCUCUCUGGCACCCAGGCUGGAGUGCAGUGGCAUGACCGCGGCUCGCUGCAACUUCCGCCUGCUUGAACUGGGUUCAAGCAGUUCUCCUGCCUCAGCCUCCCAAGUAGCUGGGACUACAGGUGCGCGUCAGUAUGCCCGGCCAAUUUUUUGUAUUUUUAGUAGAGACAGGGUUUCACCAUGCUGGCCAGGCUGGUCUCGAACUCCUGACCUCGUGAUCCGCCCACCUCGGCCUCCCAGAGUGCUGGGAUUACAGGCGUGAGCCACCGUGCCCAGCUUGCCUGGGACAGUUUCUACCUGAGUGACGCUGGGCAAGUCGCUUCCCUUCUCUGACCCUACUUGUAUCUGAAGAUGUGGCACUUAGCAGGUGCUUAAUAAACGCUAGUUUGGACUUUUAUCUGGAAGCAAAGGGGACCGCUGAUUUUAAACCUUCAGUUAAACUUGCUUGUGACCUCUUUAAAUAUACAAUUGUAAAUUUUUUAGUUGGUGGUUUACGCUGAUGUCCCGGAUUAUAGGUUAAAUUAGGAGGAAAUUUUCAGCAUGUACAUCCAUGACAGUACACACACAAUGUCAGAUUCAAAGCUCCCAAUUAAAGGCAAUCAUCUGCCUCUUGUAACAUCAGUUAAGAUCAUGUAACAUCUGGUCCCUGCUGUGUGUUGAGCUGCCUCCCAGGCCUUGGAUAUUCAUAGACUAAUGCAUUGCUUGCCAUGGGUUUGGUGUGAUUUUCCCCCAUCUUAUGGAUUAAGAAAGUGAAAAUCAGAAAUAAUGACUUGCUCAAGAUCACACACGCUAGGUUAGACACAGAUCUGUCCUGUCCCCACAUAUGUGCCCUAACCUACCACCAACCCGUUUAUUAGCAGAGACUGAGCUAUGGGCUCAGCCCACUCCAGCUAAAAAUGUGAAGAAAACGUAAGUGGCCAAGACAAGAAUGAUCAAAUAGGGUGGCAACCAACUAUAUCUGAGGACCAGAGCCAUUUUGGGGCACCAGAGCUUGUGACCUCUCCAUCUCCACCCAGCUGGGUCCAGGGGCCACUCUCAGCACUCACCUCAGCAGCUGACAUCAUAAAGCAGACUUGGGAACCUGGAAGCACUCUGGAGAACCUUUCCCUGAGACAUGGAGCUUUGGGGCCGAAUGCUGUGGGCCCUCCUGUCUGGCCCAGGGAGGAGGGGAAGUACCCGGGGCUGGGCCUUCAGCUCAUGGCAACCCCAACCACCUCUGGCUGGGUUAUCCAGUGCCAUAGAACUGGUCAGCCACUGGACUGGGGUCUUUGAGAAGAGGGGUAUCCCUGAGGCCCGGGAAUCCAGUGAGUACAUCGUGGCUCAUGUCCUUGGAGCCAAAACAUUUCAGAGCCUGAGGCCGGCACUUUGGACCCAGCCCUUGACCUCUCAGCAACUACAGUGUAUCCGGGAGCUGAGUAGCCGUCGAUUGCAGAGGAUGCCGGUGCAGUACAUCCUUGGAGAGUGGGACUUCCAGGGGCUCAGCCUAAGGAUGGUGCCCCCAGUGUUUAUUCCUCGGCCAGAAACAGAGGAACUGGUUGAGUGGGUGCUGGAAGAGGUGGCCCAGAGGUCCCAUGCUGUGGGAUCCCCAGGCAGCCCCCUCAUUCUGGAGGUGGGCUGCGGAUCAGGAGCCAUCUCCCUCAGCCUGCUGAGCCAGCUCCCCCAGAGCCGAGUCAUUGCUGUGGAUAAGCGGGAAGCUGCUAUCUCUCUGACCCAUGAGAAUGCUCAGAGGCUUCGGUUGCAGGACAGGAUUUGGAUCAUCCACCUCGACAUGACCUCAGAAAGGAGCUGGACACACCUGCCCUGGGGCCCCAUGGACCUGAUUGUCAGCAACCCUCCCUACGUCUUCCACCAGGACAUGGAGCAGCUGGCCCCUGAGAUCCGCAGCUAUGAAGACCCCGCGGCCCUGGAUGGUGGGGAGGAGGGCAUGGACAUCAUUACCCACAUUCUGGCCUUGGCACCCCGGCUCCUGAAAGACUCUGGUAGUAUCUUCUUAGAAGUGGACCCAAGGCACCCGGAGCUUGUCAGCAGCUGGCUUCAGAGCCGGCCUGACCUGUACCUUAAUCUUGUGGCUGUGCGCAGGGACUUCUGUGGGAGGCCCCGGUUCCUGCAUAUCCGGAGGUCUGGGCCAUAGCAUGGCUGCCCUGUGGAUGCCUUGUCAGUGCCGCCAGCCUGACCAGAGGGGAGGUGGAUGGCACUUUCCAGAGCCCAGGUUCUUAUGGCAUUUCCCAGGGUUCUGUGAUUUCCCCAUGCUCUGCAUUUCUAGGAUAUUUCUAGGACACCUGGAUUGGCUCCAUCACAUCAGAGUGGCUGAGGGCAGUUGCUCUGUGUUGGUGAAAUUGCUGUGGGGGUAUCGGGGGAUAUGGCCAGUAAAGUAUUGAGAGACUAACAAAUGGUGACCUAAUGUUUUGUCCAUGACUUGCAGGUCCCCUGACCCCCUUACUCCCAGGUAGCACUGGGGCAAGGGUUUCCUUCUGCCCCAGCAGGGCUGGCCGUCAGUCCCCUGCUUGGUAGUGGUGUGGGGGUGCAGUGUGGAGGAAGGCACGUGAGUCCUCACUCCUGGCCUUGGAUACCAUGGGUCCUGGCAUAGAGCAGCUCACUCCCAGGGAUUGAUUAGUCCUCCACUGCCCUGGGUGCAUGCGUACACAAUUCCCUGGCCAAGCCUGGCUCGAGCACAGGAAGCUCAUCUGCGUUUUGGCUCAAGGAUGACUGCCUGCUUUCUGGAGGGGAGGGUCUGGAGGUCUUUGCUGCACAGUUCCUGGGUCGCACAUCCACGUUCAUUUAACUGAAGGCUUGAGCCAGUGAGGGGUGUUUCCUUUUUAUCCCCAUAGCUUUUAGCUAAAACAUCCCUCCCGAGUUGACCCCCUGGGGUUUCAAAUAACCCAUGUGUCCCUGGUUGGGGCUGGGGAGAGUGAGAAGCUGAGAUACUGGGCACAGGGUUGUGGCCUCCACCCCAGCUCUGGUCUGUGCAGACUCAUGGCCACCAGGAGGCCUGCAGAUCCAGCCUUCCUGUCAACAGCGACAGGAAAUCUCUAGGUUGGUGAGUGCUGGUGAUGUGAGCCUACAUCAGGGUGGGUCCUAAGAAACAUGGCAAACCAGGCUGUCUCAUUCCACUAGACUGCCCCCUGCCACCCUGGCACUUCCCAGGGCCUGGCAGUAUGGUCUGAUGGGCAGUAUGGUCCAAUAGGCAGCAUCCUCUGCUGCAGCUGGGAGAGCUGAGUUCCAGGGCUGUGUCCUGCAGUGGGACCUUGGGCAACUCCUUUCCCUAUGAGAAGCUGGCUCUUCUGAGUCCAGGGCCAACGCCAACUGGCAACCUCUUUACUCUUAGUCAAGUGGAAUGUGCAUGCUGGCAUCUGAAUGUCCAUUCGCCAGGCAUGGAGAGCAAGAGAAGGUAUGUACUGCCUGAGGUCACAUGACAGUGACCAAGUGGAGACAGUAAGUUAGAUCCCUCCCUUUGGGGAGCCUAUAUUGCUGGAGUCAUACCCAGCCUAAGUGUUGCCCUGCACUAUGGCUGGAGGACACAUUUGGUAGAGGUCACACUGCAGCUCCCAGUGCCCCAGUGUCCUGCCCUGUGCCCAGCCCCAGCUGCAUGGACUCUGAGCUGCCCCUGGCUUCCUUUAAGGAGGCUGCUCCAGAAGGAACCUGGGUGGGGAGGGCGAAGGGGGUGCACAACCAGGGCAAGGCUCCCCACUUCCUUAGUCCCCCAUGCUCACAGACCUUUGCCUGCUAAGGUCCUCACCAGUAUUGCCCUUUCUGUCUUUCUCCUUGUGCCCUUUGGCUCUUGCUGUCUUCAGCAGCAUCUCAGGGUAGCUGCCCUGACCUCGGAGCAGUCUGUCGCCCCCCUACACCUCAGCCAGUCCUGGCUUCCCUGAUGGUCUCUCCCUCCUGGCCUCAGGCCCAUUCCUGAGGAAGGGCCUUGGCGAGCUUGUGGAUGUUGCACCAGAAGAGAGUGCAGUGUUGGAGAGUGACACUGUCGGGGCAGCUGGGGCCACAAGCAGGAGCCGGCCUCGGGCACAACUUUCUGCCCAGAAAAAUGUGCAGCUUGACUCUGCUGAGGAAAAGGUCCAAGCCAAGAGGACUGGCAGGCGGGGCCUCAAGCCUGCAGCCACUGGCUUGAUUGGGCCCUGGACGUUGAGCCCAGAUGUUGGAGCCACACCAGCCUGGAUUUCAAUCCCAGAAUCUGCCCCUCACGAGGAUGUGACCUUGGGCAGAUGACUUCACCUCACUCAGCCUUGGCUUCUAAGGCUGAGAAAUGGGACUUAAUGCUUUAUUUUAUAGGAUGCAUGUGAGGAGCCCAUGGGAUGUGCCUGGCUUGGCACAUUGUGGCAUUUUUCCUUGCCUUCCUCGGAGGGCAGACACAGGGAGGAAGGACCCAGUGCCCUCAGGCGUCCAUCUGAUGCAUGGGACCAACAUAAGGCAGGCAGGGAUACAAGGCAGUCUGGAAAGAAGGGAAGGCAGGAGUUUCAGUCUUGGGCUCUUGACUCCUCACUGUUGUCUAGAGAUGGAGCCAGCAGGCUGGUAGCCUGGCAGCCUACAUCUCCCCUCAGCCUCUCCUCACUAUGGCCCCAGUGCCUUGAGGCCCAGGCCAGGGCAGCCAGUGGCUCUAGCUCAGGGAAAGCCAGGCCCACCUGCCCUAUCCCCUCCCUUGCUCCUGAGGCCAAAGCCAGAGACUCGAACAGCCUCCCCACCACCACCAGCAUAUGUCAAGGAGCACUUGCAGGCAGAAUGGGAGGAGGACAUGGAGCUGAUGGAGUCCAGGCUGUGCAAGCCCCUGAGGUCUUGAGAGAUGUGCCCACUGCCCGUGCAGCCUCCUUCAGCCAGAGCCCAGAGCAUAGACAGGAGUGUAGGAGUCCCUGUUUGAUGUACUCUGGGAGAGUAAUUCUAUCUCCUCUUCUGAUAGUUGGGGAAACUGAGGCCUUGUCUCACAGUUGGAUGCUUUUCCCAGUUGUCAGUGGGUUUCUCCAUGGGUCUCAUACAGCUGCCUUAUUGAAAUAGGCCCCGAACCCCCUAAAUGCAAAAAAUACUCUUUUUUGCUCCUUUACCCCCACCUGGACCCUGGGCUAUUGGCUGCUCCCAAUCCUUGCCCCAAACACUUAGCUGGCUCCCCAUGACUUAAGUGUGUUCUCUUGUGUCCUAUGGAAUCCAGUUCUGAAGAGGUGGGGGAGGACAACUGUGGGAAAAGCCCUGGGGGCCCCUCCCAAGGCCCCAUCAGUGCUCUGAGUAGGCUGUCAUCAGAACAAAGGGCUCCACUGCUGACAAGGUUUGAGAACUGCUGGCUUGAGGUGAGAACCCCUUUAACCUCUGCGGGACAGCAUGUCUUUCCCUAUCCACCUUCGAUUCUUUUCUCUUUUUUUUCUUCAUUGGCUCCUUCUUAGUGGAUUCUCUUCUCUACUGCCCUGGGCUUCAGCCUUUGUGCAGUACUCUCGAUGCCCUGAACACACACCUUCCCUUUGCCCAGGCGGUGCAAACAAUCCACUUCUUCAAGCUCCAACACAAAUGCUGCCUCCUUUAGGAUGCCUGCUCUGUGCUCUCCCUGCCUCCCCUAGCCCAUACCUCUGCUGGCACCUUCUGUACCAUGCCUUCAGAAACCUUCUUAUCCCCCUCAUCUCUGGGGCCCCCUGUGGAUCUGGCAUACCCAAGUUCAGUAAAUGUCUAUCAGUAAGCUGAUGGUACAUGCAUUUUCUAGAAUAGAGCUGGGACUUCCCAUGUGGCCCACAUCUGACCUGGCAGCCCAUGUAUUCCGGUCAUUAGGGAUGGGAAGCCAUGAGGACCUGGCCUUCUGCCCGACCCAGGCAGCCAUUCAAGUUGAGCAAUGGCCACUUCGAAGACUCAAGUGCACCUGAUCCCUGCGCAACAGCCACACCAGGAGAACAGGCUGUCCUUGGCGGCAGUAGGAGCAGGCGCCAGGUUUCCUGGAGCUCUUGGCUUCAGCCAGCCCCCAGCCAGAGUCCUGGCUAGGACAGUGACCUGAUCUCCUCCUCAUGACCUUCUGCCCUGGACAAGCCCCCUGAACUGGAUUUGGGACUGUCAAAGCAACUCUACCCCUGCUCUGGUAGGCUGAACAGUGACCCCCCAAAAUGGCAGUGUCUUAAUCACCUAAACCUUAACAUGUGACUAUAUUACCUUCACAUAGCAAAAUGGACUUUGCAGAUGUGAUUAAGGAUCUUGAGAUGGAAGGAGUAUCCUGGAUUUUUCAGGUAAACUGAGUAUAAUCACAAGGGCCUCUGUAAAGGAGGCAGGAGUGUCAGAGUGACGGAAGAAAAUGUAUGUAACAAUGGAAGCAGAGGUCAGAGUGAUGCAAUUGCUGGAGGAAGAGCCAUGAGCCGAGGAAUGCAGACAGCCUCUUCUCCUCUGGGGCCUCAAGAAGAAUGCAGUCCUGCCAAUACCUUGAUUUUAAGCCCUGUGAAACUGAUUUCAGAUUGCUGACCUCCAGAACAGUAAGAUCAUAAAUUUGUGUUGUUUUCACAUGUGUGAAAACACAUGUGUGAUAAUUUGUUACAGCAGCCACGGGAAACGAAUAUAGAUUGUGGUGCCCAAAUUAGAGUGCUGCUGUAACACACGCCUACUGAUUGAAGUGGCUUUGGAAUUGCAACGUGGAAAUGGGCAGAGGCUGGAAGAAUUUUGAGAGUCAUGAUAAAUUGCCUUAACCACCUCUCUUCUGAUAGGUGAUGUGGCCAGGGGAACUCUUCCUCAACCUUCAGACCUAAACUGCCCAGGCCCCCCCUUUUUUUACUCAUAUUUGGAGAGAGGUGGCCCUUUCCCAGAGUGAGAAGACUGAAAGACUGACCAGCAUGGGUCCCAGAAGGGAGUGGGUGAGGAAUGGGACUGGGAUGUGGGGAGAAAGUGCAAGGCUGGCCUCCAUGGCCCAUCUCCAGAGACUGGGUCCAGAGAGGACCUCAGAGACUGGGACCAAGCCUGUUCCUGCUCUCCUGUGGAGUUAUGUGACUGGCCCAGGACCCCUUGGGUGUGUGAGGAUGAGCAGGGGCCCUGUACUCUCUGGGUUGCAGGUACUGCAUCUGUGAAAUGAGCACAGCAGCCCCUGACUUUGAGCUAAUGGGCCUGGCCCCUCCAUGUAAGCCAUAGGCCUGAGCAGAGCUGUGUCACCAUUCUGUUCCUAUGGUGGAGUGGGGCUAUCCCUGGGGUUCUCAACCUCCUGGUUCCUAAAACUGAAUUGGCCAACUGGUGCCCUCAGCCCUGUCCCUGUCCAAGCUGGGACUAGGACCUCCCUUUCCAGGGGUACUAAAGGACUCUGGAGACACCAUCCCACCCAGCCAAGGCUUGGGGCUCCUGAAGCCAGUCCUAACCCAGGAGCCACAUGGAGAGCUACUGGGAGGCCAGACAUGGGCCUCAUGCUGGGUUUCAGAGCUGAGAAGCUGGGGGACAGAGAGCAUGGACACCUGGGUUCAAGGGUCAGCUUGGCCCCAAAUCACCUGGAUACGCUUUGGAUGAAGCCAGGAGGGCCUGUUUAUACUGGAAGGGGUGGAUCAUGGCAAGACUUAUAUUCAAUCCCUGAUCUUUUUUCCCAGAGAGGGAUGGGGCUUACUUGAAGUAACACAGCACUUGACUCCUGACUCCCAGUAUGAUGCUCUCAUCUCCUAUUGCUUCCAAAGGCCUGGGGUUAGUUAAUUAAGUCAAUUAGGUGGUGCUCAUAUGGCUGUCCAUGUAGCUACUAAACCCAGGGAUUCUGGCCCAUAAAGCCCUCUGGGCCAGGUUUAUGGGCAGGUAAGAGUCACAUUAGGCCAACUGUAGCCCUGGGUGUGCAGACAGAUCUGAGUCCCAUCUGAAGCUCUGGUAGCUGUGGGAGGAGAGCAGGAUUUCCCCCGCUUGCGGAAUGAGUGGGUGCCUUCCCCUCUGAGGUAAUUGGCUGUACAGCCCCCAGCCUCUGCCCCCCAGGGCCCUCCUGAGGUGUCUGGAAGGACCUUUGGGAUCUUUGGCCUCAUAACCAGAAAUCAGAAGCUUCAAAUUCUAGAGGCCCCUUUUCUUCCAAAGACUACCUCUCACACAUACAGCAGUCCUGCAGGAAAAUGGUCAGGAAAGGCUAAUUUUACAGCUCACAAAGUGGGAAAGGCAGGGAAGCCUACCUCAGCUUCAUGGAAAGCCCUGAACUGGGCUGACCUCCACCUGCCCCAGCUAUGCCUAAAGGGGGAGGGUGAGACAGCUUAGAGUAGCCAUGCCCCGUGGCAGGCAGGCCUGGCUAAGUGGCCCCCUUCCCAGGGGCUGGGGUCUUCCCCAAACACUCUACCUCUCAGAGCAGAGGAUGUCACCUUAUUGCUCCCUCUUGUACUAGGUCUGCGGCCCUCUUCUGGGGCAUGUGGCUGGGGAAAUGGUGGGAUCAGAUAUCCCCUACUGAGCCCAGGGAGCAGAUUGUUGGUGCCUGAAGCGCUCACAGAGAUCCCUGUGGUACAGAUGAGGAAACUGAGGCUUAGCAGGACAGGAGCAGGGCUGGGGCACGAGCCAGGUCUCUUCUCUGGCUCACAGCUGCCAGUCCUUCCUUUGCCACCUGAAGACCCCCCACCCCACCUGGCUUUCCAGGAACAGGCCUGCCUGCCUGGAGAGGCGUCCAAGUCCCUCUGCUGUUCCUGGAAGUCAGUGUGAGGCUGAGCUACGUGACCAAGCAAAGCAAACUAGGACUACAGGUGUGAACAACCCUGCCUGGCUAAUUUUUAAUUUUUUUUUUUUUUUAGAAACGGGGUCUUGCUAUGUUGCCAGGGCUGGCACAUGGGGUUUUUAGUUGUCCCCACAUUACAAAGUUGAGGACACCAAGGCUCAGCAGGGUGCAGUUGCAGGUCAGGUUGCAUAGCUGGACAGGAAGGGAGGAUGAGGCUGCCAUUGGUGUCCAUUUGACUAUCAGAGACGCUGAGGCCAGCAUAACUAGGUCCUGGGCUGUCCCCUGCAGAGCUUAGCGCAGAAGUUACCUGGGCUUGUGGACCCUUGGAGCAGGAGCAAGGGUUUCCAGGGCUGUCCCUAGAGGGCUUUCUAGAAGACCUGCAGCUGCUCCUGGGUGCAUCUCCUGAGGUAUAGGGCCAGGGCCUCAGUCUCUCAAGACCUACUUUGUGUCAGGCACCAGGGAGAUGAUACCAAGUGGAGGGUCCUAUAGAAUAUGGUGCAUCCUGCGCCAAGUACUUCCAGGAUUAUCUUACUCAACCUUCAUGACAUCCUCAGAGAUGGAGGCUGUGAACCCUCUCGUUAUACUGACGAAGAAACAAACUGGGGCUAAGAAACUUGCUCAUAGGCUGGCUGAGCUGUGAUUCUGGCAUAGGCUGAGUGACCUGGAGCUGGAGGCCUUAGUCAUCACACCAGGCUUGAGGAGGGGCGGAUAGGACAGGAAUAUACCAGGCAGUAGGGACAGUCUGGACAAAAGCCUGGAGUUCUGCAGACAUGCGGGUAGGGAUAUGUAGGGGUGAGGUGGUGCCGAGAGGUCCCCUUGGCUGAGCUCUGAAUGCAUUUCUGGGGACCAGGGGCCUAAAGAGCUUUUUGAGCUGAGUUACAGGGUUAGAGAAGCAUUGAGGCUGCUCUUUCUGGCUGCCAGGAAAAAGGGGCUGGGGCAGGAGGCUGCAACUUGUCCAGGGUCUGGAGGUGGCUGGGGUCUGUAGCAGUGGCAUCAGAUAUUCUGGAACAGAACUGACUCACAACCAUUGCUGAGGGUUUGGAUGUGAGAUGGCCAGGACCACAGUGGGCCCAGGGAUCUGAUUGGGACCUGGGGGAAAUGGGGCCACCCUGAGUUGGAGACUGGGGUGCUGGGGGGAACAGUCGGGGAGCUUGACAGUGUAGGAUGCCUUCAGAAUAUCCGAGAAGCAGCAUUGGGGCGUCUGGAGAUGCAAAUGUGACCAUGUGGGGACACAGUCCAAAGGCAACCCUUGAGGUAGAGUUGUGAAGACCACUCUCCUAGACCUGAGUGCUGGCGACAACAGUACCGGGCAUCUGCAGUGUGUAAACUAGUGCCAGGUGCUGCACACACGUGGUCAUAAAUCCAUCUGUUGGCACAUCAGGGAUCCCUUCCUUGGCCCACUGUAUGGAUGAAGGGACUGAGGCUUAACAUGCCCAAGGUCACACAGCCAGCAGCUGGCCAUGCUGGAGUUUGAACCUAGUCCUCUGACAUCCCAGUCAGGAGAGGCGUGAGCAGGCUGCCGAGGCCAAAUGCAGCCCAGGGCCUCAACCCCCCAGAGGGGCCUCAGGAGCCAGUUAGGUGCCCCACAGCCAACGUGGGCUCCAGGGUGAAGGGGAAAGUGAUGAAUCAAACAGAAAGCAGCAGACGCAGACUGAGCUCUCUCCCUGUCGGCCCGGGUGCCAGAUUUUCACGCCCACAGCAAAGGGGCCAGGCAGAGCGCUAGGUGUGGGGCAGGAGAGGGCAGCGAAAGUGGCUGCCACUGAACCCAGACUCUGAUGUACUCCGGAUAUGGGUGGCGUGGACUGACAGACACCCAGCCCAGUUCCAGACUGAAAGUUGAGUCUGUCUCAGCAUGUGAGGAUAUGAAGUUUGCCUUGUCAUGGGGAGCAUUUCAGGUCCCUAGGCCUGUGAGGUUCUGGGAUGAGGCACCAGAUGGAUGUGUCUAAAAACCCUUGUUGAAGGCACUCCACAGCUCAAUAACUGACCAUUGCUCACUACUCUCUUGGCCCGCACUGAAAGCCACUGUUUCUUCAUCAUUUCACUCAGCCCGCCUGUCUCAGCCCCCCAGAACUUUGGAGCUCAUUCUUUCAAAGUACAUUUCAUGUGCAACUGAAAUACAUAUUUUUAAAAAGAUAAAAUGAGCAUCUAGUUAGCAAAAAUGUAUUUUGCAAGUGCAAAUUCUUUCUUAGCAUACAGUCCAUCAGGGCGAAGAGCAAUGAACACAAAUGUUUGAACUGGGGGCUGGGAUGGUAGUUGUAGUCUUAUGUUGGUCUCAAUGUCCAUUUUCUUUCAGUGUUUGAUUUUGGUAGCACAGGACAAAGUGACCGCUGAUUCUCACAGAUAAUUGUUUACAAAUGCUAGCACUGUGUCUGAAGCCCACCUUGCAGUCUCUUUGAUUGACAGGGACAGCAAGAGAAGCCUUAUCUCAAGCUCAGCACAAACCCUGUUCUCUGAGCACAUAGGAAGGAUUCUAAUGUGUCAUAAUUUGGUGCUGUGCCCAUUUGAGUCUGUGUGUGGUUUUUAAAAUUGGGUUUUUUUUUUUUCAAUAAUUAAAAAUAUGAGCUGGGCAUGGUGGCACAUGCCUGUGGUCCCACCUACUCGGGAGGCUGAGGCAGGAGGAUUACUUGAGCACAAGAGUUUAAGACAGCAGUGAGCUAUAAUAGCGCCACUGCACUCCAGCCUGGACAUCAGAGUCAGACCCUGUCUCUAAAAAAAUAAUUUUAGGCCGGGCGCGGUGGCUCACGCCUGUAAUCCCAGCACUCUGGGAGGCUGAGGCAGGCAGAUCACCUGAGGUCAGGAGUUCGAGGCCAGCUUGGCCAACAUGGUGAAAAUCCGUCUGUACUAAAAAUACAAAAAUUAGCCGGGUGUGGUGGCUCACGCCUGUAAUCCCAGCUACUUGAGAGGCUGAGGCAGGAGAAUCGCUUGAAACCGAGAGGCAGAUGUUGCAGUGAGCCAAGAUCACGCCAUUGUACUCCCACCCAGGCAACAAGAGCAAAACUCUGUCUCAAAAAUAAUAAUAAUAGGCCAGGCGCAGUAGCUCACGUUUGUAAUCCCAGCACUUUGGGAGGCCAAGGAUCACAAGGUUAGGAGUUCAAGACCAGCCUGGCCAACACAGUGAAACCCCGUCUACUAAAAAUACAAAAAUUAGCUGGGUGUGGUGGUGGACACCUGUAAUCCCAGCUACUCGGGAGGCUGAAGCAGGAGAAUUGCUUGAACCCGGGAGGCAGAGAUUGCAGUGAGCCAAGAUCAUGCCACUGCACUCCAGCCUGGGCGACAGAGCUAGACUCCAUCUCAAAAAAAAAAAUUUAAAAAUAAUAAUUUUAAAAAAAUGUUUUAAAAAUGAAAGAAAAGGAAGAAGGGAGGAGGAAGCCAGAAAGAAAGGGGCCGUGCAGGGUGGCUCACACUUGUAAUCCCAGCACUUUGGGAGGCUGAAGCAGGCAGAUCACCCGAGCUCAGGAGUUCAAGACCAGCCUGGCCAACAUGGUGAAACCCUGUCUCUACUAAAAAUACAAAAAUUAGCUGGGCAUGGUGGCUCAUGCCUGUAAUUCCAGCUACUCGGGAGGCUGAGGCAGGAGAAUCGCUUGAACCCGGAAGGCGGAGGUUGCAGUGAGCUGAGAUCACCUCACUACCCUCUAGCGUGGGCGACAGCAAGACUGUUUCAAAAAAAAAAAAGAGGAAGAGUGAAAGGAUGGACGAAAGGAACUCCUGUGGGGUGGGGCAUCUGGGGCACUUGAUGCCCCACGUGACCAUUCCCUUCCCGGAGGUCUGCCCCAACUGCUCCAGCCCCCAUAGCCUGAGGCUCCCGGCACCUCCCACCCAGCAUCUGUCACAGCAAAUCAAUCUGGGCCACAUGCUCCUGAAAGGUCCUUGGGAGCCCCACCAGGCUCCAGUGUGGUUGCCCCAAGUACUCCAUGAGUAGACAUGGGCUAGGGACUUACCCAGGCCCUUGGUGGUGCCUCCAAGGGUGGAAAGACUGGGGGACCCUGUGCCCCUGAAAGCCCAGAGUUUCACUGUUUCUGGGUACCUUCAUUUCUGGGAACUAACUGUGCUUUGGAAAGAGAGAAAUGAGAAGCAAAACCCUAGGGCCCCAGUAUCACCCCUCCUUUCUGUCUUCCUUCCGCUUAGUCACAGCCAAGAGCUCAGUACCUCAGCCUCCCUUAGGGCCACUAGGUGGGGCAGAAUACAAGGUCAGGCGAGGACACAGCAUCUGGGACGAGUCCUUUCCUGCCAACAGCCUCCGUGAGGGGUCCUAGGAUUGCUGAGGGCUGAGACCACCUUCCCAAAGUUGGGGAAGGGGUAACUGAGGCUGUCAUCUGGCCUGUCUCACCUGUCUUACCUGCAGGCCCAUCAUUCCUGCACAGUCAUUUAUUAGGCACCAACUGUAAGCCAGGCCCAGGAGGUUGGAUGGUUCAGGUGGGGCCCUGGCCUUGCAGAACUCAUGGACUUGCACAUAGACUCCUCCUGACAGGCCCCUCAUGAGUAGCUGGGUCCUUACGAUUUUUCUGGUCAGCAGUGGGGAGCCGUGGGAGGCAUUAGGCUCUGGGGAAGCCAAGCAACAUCACAUGUACACAGCAUAGAGACUCACACACCCUUGCACAGGCACCCACACGUACGUGUAUGUUCAUGGGCGUGGGCCUUGAGCACCGGGUCCCGUGAGCCACUGCACCUGGCCAACUGGGUCCAUGUCCAUAAUCAUAGGUGUCCACGCAGGGCCUCCCUUGGAUGGGGGAGCUCCAGGCUCUGGAAACCAAGCCAGGGUUGCAUGCAUGCACGUGUGUGUGUGUGUGUGUGUGUGUGUGUGUGUGUUUGUGUGUGUGUGGUGUUACUCUGCCUCAGAGGCCCAACCACUGCCUCCAAGUCAUGGGAGCGCAGAGCCCAUGUAAGCUCAAACACUGCCCCAUGUCAUAGAAAAGAGGGCCAAAGAUGGGGCUGGGCGUGGUGGCUCACUCCUGUAAUCCUAGCACUUUGGGAGGCUGAGUCGGGUGGAUCACGAGGUCAGGAGAUCGAGACCAUCCUGACUAACACGGUGAAACCCUGUCUCUACUAAAAAUACAAAAAAAUUAGCUGGGCGUAGUGGCGGGUGCCUAUAAUCCCAGCUACUCAGGAGGCUGAGGCAGGAGAAUGGCCUGAACCCGGGAGGCGGAGCUUGCCGUGAGCGGAGAUUGCACCACUGCACUCCAGCCUGGACGACAGAGUGAGACUCCGCAUCAGAAAAAAAAAAAAAAGAAAGAAAAGAGAGCCAAAGCUCAGAGAGGGCCCAUGACUUGCCCAGUGUCACACAGCAAGGUGAGGCAGGUCUGGGAGGGAAAUGAACCAGACCUUAUCCACAUCCCUGACCUUUUUGGCUUCAUGCUUGGAGCUUGGCACCCCCUGAGAACCACACUCCGUUGACCUCUGGGAAAUGGAGGCUGGUGAUUCUCCCAGCAAACCCGCCUGGGAACUAACCACAGGCUCCUCCCAGCUUUCACUAACCAACCCCAGGAUUUCCAAUACCGGUGCUUUGCUUAGCUGUACUGGGCACCUGGAACUCAUUCUCCCUGCCACCCUCCCUCCCUGAUUCCUUGAAUAAAAUUCAGCCUUCCAAAUUUUACUCAAAUGCUUCUACUUUCUCUGACCCUCUGGAACUUUCCCCUGUUGCCAGCCUCCCUCCAGCAUCUGUCCCCUCAUUCCCACCUCCUGUUUACUUCCCUACAAAAGCCAAAAAUUGACCCCUAGAGCCUGAGACUCUGGAUGGAGGAUCUUCGUAGCUGGGGCCACACCCAGGCCAGCCCAGCCCUUCAGACUCUGCCAGUCACAGUGGGGUGGGCCCUGGAGCUGGAAGAGGAAACAGAGCCUCUGCCAGAGUCACCACCUGCCCCCAACCCUACUUCUCCUCCGAAGGCCCAACAAGGUCCUGUGCGCCCUCCAAGGGCAGAGGAGGCUGCUGGCUGUGGCUGUGGGAGGAGACCUGGAGCACUGUGCCCGAGGCAAAGCUGGCCCCGUGGAGUUUGCUAUUCCAGCUUUUAUUUACUCCUCUGUACCCUGAGCACCAUCAACUGGGUGCCAGGCCUGUGCCUAUAUUUGGCAGGGUGAGGGGUGGGGGCCAGACAAAUUGUAGAGGAGCCUCAGGUCUUUGGGGUGUUGCCCCUCCACUACAUGGCCCCAGACCAAGUUCUCUGCCAGUUUGCAGAGCUCUUCCCUUCCACUUGGUCUUGAGGAGGGGCCAGAGAGGCUGCCUUUACCCCAUGAGCUCUGAACCCUCUCACUAUCUGGCUGUCCCCUCAUUCUCUCACCACCCACUCCCACUCCCGAUGGGAGCCUCAGGCCUGGCUUAGGAACCCUGCCCACAGCUGUACUAAUGCCCUUGGCUUUGCUAUAGGGAAAGAACACAGCCACUCCACACUCUGGGACAGCCAGCUUGCGUCCAUCCCCUAGUGCAGAGGGCUAGUUUAGGGAAGGACAUUAGGACCCUGACUGUGCACCUGACUCAGGGGCCCCGGAGAAGAUUUGGUGGGCUAAGGGUGGGCAGGAGAAUACAACUCACAGCCAAGCGGAAGGUGGCUUUCAGCUCCCCCCUUCUCAUUUUUUCUUACUGUGGCUGCACCAGGGCUGUGCCCCUCAUGGAAGGUUCACUUUCCUGCUUAUCUAGUCUCAGAUGUUACAGUUUUUCUUGUUAUGUAUUAUACAGAGAGAUGGCCUAACUGGUUCUUGCUGCUGCAUGGGCAAGCCAUUAAUUUACAGGGGUUUAUCUUAUAACUGGACACCUUUUUGUUUUCUCUUACAAGAUGUGCUUGUUGUUGCUUCUCUUGGAUUUUCUACAUUGACAUUUUACCACUGAAAAUAAUGACAAUGACAAAUUUGUCUUUUCCUUUCUUUCUUUUUUUUUUUUUUGAGACAAAGUGCCACUCUGUUGCCCAGACUGGAGUGCAGUGGCGCGAUCUCCCAGGUUCAAGCGAUUCUCUUGGCUCAGCCUCCCGAGUAGCUGGGAUUACAGGCGUCCACCACCAUGCCAGGCUAAUUUUUUUUUUGUAUUUUCAGUAGAGACGGGGUUUUGCCAUGUUGGCCAGGCUGGUCUCGAACUCCUGACCUCAAGUGAUCUGCCACCUCGGCCUCCCAAAAUGCUGGGAUUACAGGCCUGAGCCACCACACCCGGCCUGUCUUUUCCUUUUUAAUACUUAUGGCUCUUAUUUAUUUUCCUUGUUUAAUAGCUUGGCUGAGACCUUCAAUACAAUAUUGAAAAACUGUAACGACUAGAGCAUUUGUAUAUUGUUUCUCACUUGGGGUGCCUCUGGUCCCUCCCUGUCAAGUGCACUUGCUAUUGAUUUUGGAUAGAUGGCCCUUUUCUACUUAAAAAUGGUUCAGUCUAGUUCUGGCUGACUCUGAUUUUUUGUUUAUUUUAGAGGCUUUUUUUUUCAUCUUUCAUUCAUGCAACAGACCUUCAGUGAGCUGAUUGCCAGGACUACACUGUCAUACUGUGGUACCAAAGAAAAAUUGACACGGUCCCUACUCAUAAGGAGUUCAUGGCCUGGUGGAGGAUACAGGCAGGCAAAUAGAUCCUUAUCCUUAGGCCAUGGGGCAUGCAUUCAGUCACCAUCUGCUGGCACUGUGCCAGGCACAAGGAAUGGGCACUAUUCAGGCAGGCCCCCAUCACAGUCUGGUGGGGUCCAAGCAGUUCACAUCCCCUCUCACUCAAGUUCCCACAGAGUAGUUGCAAUGGUGAGCUGAGGUUUUCUCUGCUGCAGAGGCCAGGUGGGUAAGUAACCAAAAGUGCCUGAGAGCUAAUCCCCUGGAGCAGCCUGAAACCAAGGAAGACAGAGAGUUGGUAGACACAUGCCCAGCUCCCUCACCCCUUGGGUGGGACAACCGUGGCUUGUGUUUUCUGCCAGCUCCCAACUGAAGACUGAGCCUCAGUUGCCUACAGAAGGAACCCACUCAUAAACCCACCUACCUCCUUUGGCUUCCUUUCCUUCCCUGUCUCACCCCCUCUCCCAUUUUAUAUCAAUAAGUGUGAAGGCUGAGAUUUUAUCCGACUUUCUUUUUUUUUUUUUGAGACAGAGUCUCAUUCUGUUGCCAGGCUGGAGUGCAGUGGCGUGAUCUUGGCUUACUGCAACCUCUGCCUCCCAGGUUCAAACGAUUCUCCUGCCUCAGGCUCCCGAGUACUGGGACUACAGGUGCGCACCACCACACCCAGCUAUUUUGUAUUUUUAGUAGAAACAGGGUUUCACCAUGUUGGCCAGGAUGGUCUCAAUCUCUUGACCUCAUGGUCUGCCCACCUCGGCCUCCCAAAGUGCUGGGAUUACAGGAGUGAGCCACCGCGCCCGGCUUAUCCGACUUUGAAGCAAACAAGUUAGUCUAUCAUAGUCUAUCAUAUUCUCAAGGAUCAUGGCAGAAGGCACAGAACUCUGGGUUCAGAAACAGACAACAGAUUAUUGUUUACAGUAACGGCAGUAGACAGAGUAAAAGCAUUUUCUUGCACCACUUCCCUGAACCGCAGUUCCUACAGAGUGAUGUGAUGAUGGCCCGGUGAUGCCUGCAUAUGCAUUGGGUUGCACUACGGUGGAGAAACUGCAUGCUGAAUUUAGGGGACCCACGUCUUUUAUAAUAAGCUGCAAGCAAACCUGCCCAGGUGGGAGAUGUUAUCUUUAGUAUACGGGACAAUAAAAUCUGCCUUUUGCUCUGGAGGGAGAUACUACCUCUAUCUUCUAAGGUUACUCACUAUAAUAAUCACCCUUGUAAAGAUUAUUUAGAACAAGGGCAACCAGUGCCUCUACUGGCAAGUGUGCAGAAAUAGGAGAGAACCAUGGGGAAUUGUCUCUCAAUACCUUACUGGUGCUUCUUGGCAUUACUUCCCAAAUAAUCUAUUUGCAUUUGGAUGCUUGUCUCAGAGUGGUUUCUGCAGGAAAAAACCCAAGAUAGAGAGACAACACUAUAUAGGCAUCGAUGUAUUUCUGGGGUGACUCUCUUUCCUCCAGACCUCUCCUGCAAACAACGCAGGGGAGCCACGCAAAGGAAGAGGUUUCCACACCUGGGAUUGAUACUGCUGGGACUCCAGGGCAGGUGCUCUAAAGGACUCUUAGAAUUUCAUUUUUAAUGUUUAAUAUUUGGUCCAUCUAGAAUUUAUGGUGGAAGGUGUGAGGUAGACGUUGCACUUUUUUUUCCUUCCAAAUUGCUCCAAUAUCACUUACUGGAAAUUGUGCUUUGUCUGUUACCACUCUCUUCUAAUCUGCCUGUGGCCUGUUCCUUAGAGUGUAUCACAAACAUACAAGUGAUCAAUUUCCAAUAAAUUGAUUAAAGAA